GUAUCAUUCAGUUCUUUUGACAAAUUAAUCAUUUUCCUUUGUUUUUGAUCUUAUAUCUCAGGCUAUAUAGUAAAAUUCUAGAGAAGUAACAUGUACACUGGCAGUUUUACUGCCAAAGUUAGCUAGAAUAAUUCUAAUCAAAGCAAAAGGGUUAUGAUUGGGUGACAGUGUGUUUAAUUUCUAGAAUUAUCAAGUGUUAAUUGGGCUUUUCUGUUGUUAAGUGUUUGCUUAGCAGAGUACUAUGCCUAUGGCAGGUACUGGUAGUUAAGUACCUGCUCACCUGUGGCACUAUGCAAAAUUUUUAAAAUUUUGUUUCCAGAAUUAGAAUUUGUAAUAGCCAUGACAUGUAUGUGUGUGGUUCUCCCUUGCUGAUUCUCUUUAAUUUAUAAAUGUUUUAGAAUAUUUAUCUAAGGAAUUCUCAUGGUAAUUACUUAAGAACCAAUACCAGCAUGUUAAAACAUAAUUAGAAAGGAUCUUUUAAAGGUUUUAUUGUAAGAAAAUAUACAGAUUAAAACUGCACUGAGAUAACAUGUCAACAAUCAGGCAGAAAUCCAAAAGUCUGACAAUAUACUGCAUUGGUGAGGACUUCAGAAACAGACCUUCUCUUGCAUUGCUGGUGGGGUGCUUGUGGUACCACCCUCAUGGAGGUGAAUUUGGCAAUGUCUAGCAAAAUUACCUAUGCAUUUACUUUGUUUUCUUUUCCCCCAUUCCUCUCUUUCCUCAGUCCCUGGUAACCUUUAUAUGUUUUCUGUCUAUGAAUUUACCUAUUAUAGAUAUUUCAUAUAUAAAUAACAAUCAUACAAUAUUUGCCCUUUUGUGUCUGUUGCUUUCACUUAGCAUAUUUUCGAGGUUUGUCCCUGCCAUAGUGUCUAUCAGAACUUCAUUCCGUUUUAUAGUGGAAUAAUAUUCCAUUGUUUGGACAUAGUGCCUUUAGCUCAUCUGCUGAUGGACACUUAGAUUGUUUCUGUAUUUUGGCUUUUCUGAAUAAUACUGUUGUGAAUAUUUGCAUACACGUAUCUGAGUCUAUUUUUAGUUGUUUUGGAUAUAUACCCAGGAGUAGAAUUAAUGGGUCAUAUGAUAAUUGUCUGUUUAACAUUUUAAGAACUAGCUAAACUAUUUUCCACAUUGACCGCAUCAUUGUACAUUCCCACCAGCAAUGCACCAAAGGUUCCAAUUUCUCUACAUCCUUGCCAACACUUGUUUAAAAAAAUAAUAGUCGGCCAGGCGCGGUAGCUCACGCCUGUAAUCCCAGCACUUUGGGAGGCCGAGGCGGGCAGAUCAUGAGGUCAGGAGUUCGAGACUAGCCUGACCAAGAUGGUGAAACCCCAUCUCUACUAAAAAUACAAAAAUUAGCCGGGCAUGGUGCUGUGCACCUGUAAUCCCAGCUACUCAGGAGGCUGAGGCAGGAGAAUCACUUGAACCCGAGAGGCAGAGGUUGCAGUGAGCCGAGAUUGCACCACUGCACUCCAGCCUGGGCGACAGAGCAAGACUCCGUUUCUAAAUAAAUAAAUAAAUAACAGAGCAAGACUCCAUUUCUAAAUAAAUAAAUAAAAUAAAAUAGUCAUCCUAAUGAGUAUUAAAUGGUAAAAGUUUUUCAUUUUAAUGAAGUCCAAUUUAUCUAUUUUUUCUACUAUUGCCUGUGCUUUUGGUAUCUAUUUAAGAAACCGUUGCCAAGUCCAAAUCAUGCAGAUUUCCCUGGUGUUUUCUUUUAAGAGGUUUAUAGUUUGAACUCUUAAGUUUAGGUCUUUGGUCCAUUUUGUGUUAAUUUUCGUAUACUGUGUAAAGUAAGGGUCCAGCUUCAUUGUUUUGCCUGUGGAUAUCCAGUUGUCCCAGUAUAUGCGUUUACUUUUGAUCCAGCAAUCUCACUUCUAGGAAUUUAUCUUAACAAUACGCUGACAAAAAUAUGAAAAGAAAUAGCACAGGGCUAUUCAUGCAACACUGUAAUAUCCAAAGACUGGGAACAACUUACAUGUUCAUCAGGAGAGGACCUGUGGAAUAAUCCAUAUUUAUAUAAUUAAUCCAUAUAAUGAAGGACCGUGGAGCUGAGACAGGAAUGGGAGAUCGCUAGGAUAUGCUGAUAUGAAGACAAACAUGCCUAUCAUCACAUCAAAGAGGUAUCAGCAUAGUGUUGAGUGGGCAGCAGAGCUGAUGCGUAGACAGGGGCAGGAUGAGAGUACAGUGCGCAGAAUCCUCAAGGAUUACACGAAACCGCUUGAGCAUCCUCCUGUGAAAAGGAAUGAAGAGGCUCAAGUGCAUGACAAGCUUAACUCUGGAAUGGUUUCCAACAUGGAAGGCACAGCAGGGGGAGAGAGACCUUCUGUGGUAAACGGGGACUCUGGAAAGUCAGGUGGUGUGGGUGAUCCCCGUGAGCCAUUAGGCUGCCUGCAGGAGGGCUCUGGCUGCCACCCAACAACAGAGAGCUUUGAGAAAAGCGUGCGAGAGGAUGCCUCACCUCUGCCCCAUGUCUGUUGCUGCAAACAAGAUGCUCUCAUCCUCCAGCGUGGCCUUCAUCAUGAAGACGGCAGCCAGCACAUCGGCCUCCUGCAUCCUGGGGACAGAGGGCCUGACCAUGAGUACGUGCUGGUCGAGGAAGCGGAGUGUGCCAUGAGCGAGAGGGAGGCUGCCCCAAAUGAGGAAUUGGUGCAAAGAAACAGGUUAAUAUGCAGAAGAAAUCCAUAUAGGAUCUUUGAGUAUUUGCAACUCAGCCUAGAAGAGGCCUUUUUCUUGGUCUAUGCUCUGGGAUGUUUAAGUAUUUACUAUGAGAAGGAGCCUUUAACGAUAGUGAAGCUCUGGAAAGCUUUCACUGUAGUUCAGCCCACGUUCAGAACCACCUACAUGGCCUACCAUUACUUUCGAAGCAAGGGCUGGGUGCCCAAAGUGGGACUCAAGUACGGGACAGAUUUACUGCUAUAUCGGAAAGGCCCUCCAUUUUACCAUGCAAGUUAUUCUGUCAUUAUCGAGCUAGUUGAUGACCAUUUUGAAGGCUCUCUCCGCAGGCCUCUCAGUUGGAAGUCCCUGGCUGCCUUGAGCAGAGUUUCCGUUAAUGUCUCUAAGGAACUUAUGCUGUGCUAUUUGAUUAAACCCUCUACUAUGACUGACAAGGAAAUGGAGUCACCAGAAUGUAUGAAAAGGAUUAAAGUUCAGGAGGUGAUUCUGAGUCGAUGGGUUUCUUCACGAGAGAGGAGUGACCAAGACGAUCUUUAACAAUUCAACCUCAAAUUUCUAAUUUCACCAACAACUAUUUAUUGAGGGCUAGGUAAAAAGUUCUUUUUGUUGUAAUCGUCCAUUAAUUCAUAAGUUUUAAAGGGCAUGGUGCUCCCAGCACCAGAAAACUAUCAGUGUUUUUAAAGAUAAAUUACACAAGGGAGGAGAAAGAUCCCUGUGCUAGGACUGCAGAUUCUAUACUUGCGUUGGCCUCUAACUCUCCAAUCCAGAGCCUCCUGCCUCUGGCGUCAGUCUUUUCCCUCAUCCACUCACUGGGGAGAUUGGACUAGAGGAGUCCUGAGAGGACACUUCCAACAAGAGACAUUUAUUCUCUGAUUUUACCUGAAAAUGGUAGUAGUUUACAUUUAUACAGUACAGUUUAUGAAGCACUUUCAUACGCAGGCAUCUCUUGUUACCUACAUCUAAGCUGUUCCCGAAAGAGUGUUACAGAACACAACAGUAUUGUACAAUAUUCGAUAAGCAUAUCUUCACUGCACUUGUUAUAAAAAUGAGUGGUGAAAUAAUGUUUGGAGACAUAAUGAAAGCGAUUAACAUUUGGCAAAAUAUAAUAAAGCCUUUUUGUAAUUGGUGAGAAAGUCAUGAAGACUUAAGUUGCCUCAGGGCAUCUGGUGGCAAGAGGAGGGAGAUGGGUGGCUGGGCAUGGUGGCCCAUACCUAUAAUCCCAGCACUUGGGAGGCCUUGGGAGGCCAAGGCGCAUGGAUCGCUUGAGCCCAGGAGUUGGAGACCAGCUUGGGCAACAUGGUGAAACCUCCUCUCUACUAACAAAAAUUAUCCAAGCAUUGUAGCACAUGCCUGUAAUUCCAGCUGCUCAGGAGACUAAGGUAGGAGGAUCGCUUGAGCCCAGGAGGAAGAGGUUGCAGUGAGCGGAGAUUGUGCCACUGCAAUCCAGCCUGAGCAAUAGAGCAAGGUCCUGUCU